ACACAAAGAGGUUCUUCUUAGUGGAGGGAGAGCAGAUGUAGGGCAUCCUACCGAGAAUUUCCGGAACCACGUGCGAGAUGAUGCCAGUCAUGAACGUCUCCGCGCUUCCUUUCGCUUUGGAAAUAUCCUUAAGUAGAAAUUUUCUGAGCUUUGCCUAAAACUAGAAUCUGUGUUGAGGUUUUUCAAAAUUAAGUAACGCCAGAGACAUACUGUGACGUGAGGAAACGCUCUUAAAUGAAAUUUUAAGAUCUAUUUGAGAAACAUGUACUAAAAAUGUACUGACCUCCUAUUAAUGCCAGGCGCUAUGCUGAAUUCUGGGCCUUCACAUUGUCCUUCCAUUAUUAGAACUGAAGCCCAGAUUAUUUGAAACAAAAAAUAAACUUCAAUAAUUUAUUAAAAUUUGCAAAGGAACAAAAUUUUACUUCACAAUUGUACAUUUCGUUUUCGUAAUUUUUAGGACAAAAUAGCUUAAUUGACUCUUCUGUCAUACAAAUAAUCAGCUGAAGGAAAUGGCAUUUAAGAGCAUCGAACAAUAAUAAAUGUUUGAUUAAAUAAAAACCGUGACAAGAGAGUAGGGAGGAGAAGGUCCUAUGUCGCUCACUGAUGCACUUAACAAACAUUUGUCAACUCCUAGGAGUUGCAUUCUGUACAAAAUGCACAACAAUUCUUACUUAAGUUCAUAAUAUAGUAAUUCAUUUGAGCUGAAUUUCCUUCCAGUCCUAAAGACACAGCCAAAACUAUUCGAAAAGUGGGGGAAGGUGUUUUGUUUUGUACUUUAACAAAAAGGGGAAGAGAAACAAAUUUAAAAGAGGGGAAGAGUCAUUUUUCAUUUAUUAAAAUAAGCAUUCCUACACCUUUUAGAAAGUAAAGCAGUGAUGUGCAUGCUGUUAAUUCAGAUUUAUGCAUUUAUUUAUUUAUUUUGAAACGGAGUCUCAUUCUGUCGCCCAGGCGCGGCCAAUUUUUGUAUUUUUAGUAGAGAUGGGAUUUCACCUUAUUGGUCAGGCUGGUCUCGAACUUCUGACCUCAAGUGAUCCUCCCGCCUCGGCCUCCCAAAGUGCUGGGAUUAGAGGCGUGUGCCACCGCGCCCGGCUAUUAUUUGAUUUUUAUUAGUUAUCUCAAACUCUUACUUGGUCCUGAAAUCGUUAUUUUAUUUUAUCCUAAGGAUACUAUGAAUCUUAAAAUUCUUUUUCUUGGCUACUACAAACUUAGAACCAAGUGUGCAGCCUGCCUUUAGCAAAUGUACAGGCAUCACUAAUUCAUUUAUUUAUUCUUAUAUUUAACACCUAUUAUGAUACAUAGUAUGAGGUGCUACAGAUUUAGUAGUAAAAUAAAUGCAGUCCUAGCAUGAGUGGAGAAGUUCAUCUUGUACCAUUUAAGAGAGACAUUAAAUGAAUAACCUCAAAUGUGAUAGUAGGAUGAAAUUGAGUGGGGUCACCAAGUCUUAGGGGAUAGGAAGGUCUCUUUAAUUACUGACUUUUCAGGCCGGAGGCAGUGGCUUAUGCCUGUAAUCCCAGCACUUUGUGGGGCUGAGGCCAGGCGGGUGGAUUACCUGGGGUCAGGAGUUCCAGACCAGCCUGGCCAAUAUGGCAAAACUCUGUCUCUACUAAACAAACAAACAAAAAAAUUAGCUGGGCAUGGCGGUGCACACCUGUGAUCCUAGCUAAUCGGGAGGUUAAGGCAGGAGAAUAGCUUGAACCCGGGAGGUGAAGGUUACAGUGAGCUGAGAUCGGGCCACUGCACUCCUGCCUGGGUGACACAGCAAGACUCCAUCUCAAAAAAAAAAAAAAAGGAAAAUGGAAAAAAAAAGGAAAAGAAACCAACUUUUCAGUUGAAAGUUCAAAGCUGAGUGUUCAGAGGAGCCUUCAAGGCUACAGGAAUCCUUAAUUUUUUUUGCAGGUAUCUGAGUUGAAAGAACCAGGCCUAUUUAAGGAGGUGGAAAAAAUCCAAAAAAGCUUUGAUUCAGAAUGGGGAUGACAGUGUAUGGCAAGAAUUAUGCAGAUUAACUUUAGCUUCAUACCUUUCUACUUAUCUGUUUAAAUCUUGAUUUUAAAUUCUUCCUUGAGCAUAGUAACGUAUAAACUCCUACAUAUUUCAGAUUAGUCUAUUUUCAUUAAAUAAAAUGUCUAUGAAGUUUCCCCCUCUAAAGAAAGAAAAGCCUAGCAUUUCAACCUAUAUUCUUGAGGCAGGGUGGGGAGGGAUACAAAAACUUAAUUAUAAUGCAAAGCAGAUUUUAUAUAUUUUGAAAAUUUUAAGAAUUUUGCUAUGAGAGACUAGAUAGAAACUGACAGGAGAGUUCUGGGAAGACUACAGAGGACUGAUACUUGAUUUAGGCCUCAAAGUGUUUGAACAAUCAUGGGACAGAAGAAAAUCCAAGUGAGAGAAAUAAUAUAAGCAAACAAGCAAAGAAGCUGGAAGUGGACCCUGCCUGAUUUCGUCUGUGACCAAAUCUGGACUCCAGAUUACUCUGCUAAAUGUAGUGACUACGAUAUUACAAAUUUACUAUGCCUAUUCCUUGACAGCCUCUGUGGGGAUGAUGGCUGGCGAAACUUCUUUGCAAAUGACUCUAGAGACUAAGUGACUACUGUGAUCAUAGCAGAAUGGCAAUAUUCCUUUAUGCUAAGAAAAGCCCCACUGACACUGACCCUAUUCCCAGGCAGUUCUCUCACUUUGGGCUUGGAGUACUGCCCUUUUAUAGGAUGCUUCCUGAUCCAUUAUUUGGAACUACCAAAAUGCUUUAAUGAGAUCAUUUUAAGUGUCAUAUCUUUAAGUGCUUUGUAUAAAUCAACAGUUGGAAAAUAUUCCGUAUUUGUGAACUGUGUUAUAGUUACAAUAAUGGAAGUUUCAGCAAACCUCUCAUUCUUCAACAAAGUAAUCCUAAAUUUGAAAUUAUUAGUGUACUUAAAAAUCAAUGAAUAACUGGAGCAAUAUCUAACUGCAAGAGAAUCCCAAGAAAUGUGAUACUAAAAUCUCACUUAUAAGUAAAUUGUGCUAGUAAUAAAGAUGCAAAAUUAAUAACUGGUAUUGUCUUUACAGAGGGAUCUCCAUUUAAUUUUCCUUUGAUGAGCACAGUUCUUGCUGAAUCCCGUCUAUCACCCAAUGGCACCCACUUUUUCCUCCCUUGGAUAUGCAGUGGUUUUAUGAUUUAUUUAUUUAUUUAUUUAUUUACUCAAUUAUUUGGCAACCUUAGGCUUGGUAUUGUGAUAAAGAUUUGAAAUAUAAGGAUGAAUAGUCUAGUCCCUACUCUCUAGGACUCACAAUUUGGUAAGUGAGAUAGAUGCAUAAACAAAUAACUGUGAUACUACAUUAUAAGUGAGAAAUAAAAGAAAUAGCAAAGUGCUCAGAGCACUGGACAUAGAGUCACAAAAAAUAUCUCUACCAGAGAGAUCAAGAGAACCACAAAGAAGGUGACAAUUAAGCUUUCCCUAGAAGAGUGAAUCAGAUUUCUUCAGAGGGAGACAGUGAAGGUAAAAGAUCAUUUUGGUUAGCAUGAGGAAAGGCAUGGAGGUGUAACGGUAUAAGAUGUUUGGGAUGUUGUGACAUUACAUUGCAUCAAGUCUACCAAUAACAAUAUAUAAACAUAUCUGUUUCAUACUUUGUAAUGAAACCAUCUGUUAAUUGAGACCUUACCUCACUUUUUAUUGAUUUUCCCCUUAGUUUAGUUUCUUUACAGUCAGAUUUUUUUAAAACUGUAGGUCAUAAAACAAAUUUAGCAGCUCUCUAAUAGCAUUUCUUUAAAAUUGAAUAGCAUAGAAGAGACUAUAAUAAUGUCAAGUAGAAAAAUAUCAGAGUGCAAUAUAAUAGUAAAGUACGUAAUGUUUUUGUGAAACAUACUUAGUUUAUUUGUGUCUAAGUGUUCUAUGUGUCUGUUCCAUAAUGUAUUUCAUAUUGUGGGUCACAAUAAAAAUUUGAAAGCCACUGCAGUAGUAAUAUUUUCUAUUGCUUUUCAUUGCACUCUUGUUAUAUUGGCUAUGAUUAAACCUUGAGUCCAAAUGAACCUAGGUUUUUAAUGAAGUGACAAGUGACACAGACUGACCUCAUUUAUAAGCCUGGCACACAGGCAAGCAUCUGUUUUAGUGAACUCUAGUUACAUUUUACCAGAUGAAAUGCUGCUAGCUUGGGAGUGAAACUAUCAUUUGUAAUGUUAUUUUAACAUUGCUUUUCUAUUCUGGAUUCUAAACUAUUAAAUUAGAGACAAUAUAUAAAGAUAUAACCAAUUAGUUGUAUAUUUUCUAAGACACCAGCUUCUAAAAUAAUCAUUCAUUUCUUUCAACAAUUAUUGAGUGUCUACUAUAUGUCUAAUGAUAUUCUACAUGCCAGAGAUGUAGUGGUGGAAAAGACAAGAAAGGUUGUUGAAAUAAACAUAUUUUACAUUAAACAUUUAUAUUAUACUUGAGGUACUUGUGAUUAAAGUAACAUGACAUAGACUUUUUUAAGAUUUAGAAGCAAACUACAAGAUAAAGAAAGAAAGAAAACUUAAAAAAAAAACACCUUCAACUUAGACAACAGACGUCACACCACAGAAGGUACUGCAUAGGAUAUUUAAAACUAGAUGAGGCAGGGUGUGGUGGCUCAUGCCUCUAACCCAGAAACUUUGGAGGGUUGGGGUAGGGCAUCAUGUGAGGCCAGGAGUUUGAGACUAGCCUGGGCAACAUAGUGGGACUGUGUCCCUGGGCAACAUAGUGGGACCGUGUCUCUGCAAAAAAAAAAAAAAUAAAAAUAAAAAAUUAGCCACAGUUGGUGGCUGUGUUAGUCUGUUUUCACUGUGCUAUAAAGAACUACCUGAGACUGGGUCAUUUAUAAAGAAAAGAGGUUUAAUUGACUCACAGUUCUGCAUGGCUGGGGAGGCCUCAGGAAACUUACAAUCAUGGGGAAAGGCAAAGGGGCAGCACGGCAUGUCUUACAUGGCAGCAGGAGAGAGAGAAAGAGAGAGGGGAAGUGCCACCCUUUUAAAACCAUUAGGUCUUGUGAGAACUCCCUCACUAUCAUGAGAACAGCAUGCGGGAAACGGACCCCAUGAUCCAGUCACCUCCCACCAGGUCCCUCUCUCAACAUUUGGGGAUUACAAUUCUAGAUGAAAUUUGAAUGGGGACAUAGAGCCAAACCAUAUCAGUGGUGCUCACUUGUGGUCCCACCUACCGUGACACUGAGAUGGGAGGAUAGCUAGAGCCUGAAGGUCAAGGCUGCAGUAAGCCAUGGCAACGCCACUGCAAUAGCCCUUCUCAAAAAAAAAAAUAAAAAAAUAAAAAAUAAAUGAAUAAAAGUAGAUAAGACAAAUGGCAUAUUUCACAAAAUGAUUUUUAAUCUAUUUCUUAUGUAAAAAUUAGAAAACAUAUGCUUAUACCUAACACAAUUUGCCAGAAAAAAAUGAGUCUUGCACAGGAGGGAAUUAAUAUUUAUGCUACUGUUGUGUUGUACUUAAAAAGUUUAAAGUUCUCCACUGAGAGUAAAGUAAUAGAUUUUUUAAAUUGCAUAUUAGAUGGAGAGUAAACCUUGAACUUUACAUAUGAAAUUUCUUUGAUUUAUCCUUGUAGUUUUAUAUAUGAAUGGUGGUGAAAAGUAAUAGCAUUUAUCGUUUAAAAUUUCAGAAACAGUCUGUUUUUAUUCGUAACACUAUUUGUAAUGACUAUGCUAGGAUUUAUAAAAUUUAUUCUCUUUGCCUUAUGACAUUAAAAAACUAUAAUUCAAAAUAUGUCAAUUGAAGGCCUUAUAUUAUAGACUAAGAUGCUAGGUUGGGAAAAAUAAACAUAUUUGACCUCACUGAGGAAGUAUGUCAACAAAAUGUAAGUAAAUGAUUUAAGUUAUUAUUAAAUAUAUGUCUUCAUGUAUUUUUUAAUACCAUUGCAUGUCUUCAUACUGCUUUCUGUAUCAUUAUUCUCACUUGCUUCCCAAGCUGUCUUUUGUCAUUUUUAACUGCUCCUUUGAAGCUGUUUAGGAAUAUAAGUCUUUCUUGGUCACUUCUGGAAAUUUAUUUUACCAAAUUUAACCCAGUGGCUGUUUCCGUGUUAUUUAAUUUUUUCUCAAAGUGUCCUCUAACCUCAAUCAUUUAUUGAAGGUUUGCUUCACUUUUCAGAGUGAGUACUACAUAUAUUAUUUUCAUUUGGGAGAAGGACUAAGAGAGAAAAGGAGAGUUAUCUACAUAGGAGGGAAAAAUAACGUGUUUUAUUGAUCAUUUUUAAACUCAAAAAAGUAUUUAUUAGAGAAAUGAGAAAAUUCAUGUUUGAGACAAUGUUGAAAGUUUAGAAUGUGGGACACACAUAGUAAUGCAGAAAUUUCCCGUGUUAAAGUCCUCUAACUGUGAUCACUUGAAAAUAAAAACUAAACUGUUUAAAUCUGGCUUGACUUCUUUUUAAUGGUGUUAAGUUUCAAGGAUGUAUUUAAACAUUUUUCAUCUUAUUGAAGUAUUUGCUUCCUUUGCAUUCACAUUAGAGAAGCUAUAGUUGCUUCAGUUGGACUACAUUUUCCUAAGGUGAACAGUUUGGGUUGAGUCCACACUAAACUAAGAAAAUACUUAGACAAAAGAUUAUCUUUGACAAAUAUAUCAGUGAGUGAUCAGAAUAUAUAAAUAGAAAUAUUGAUUUUGAAAAACAAGAUAAAAAUCAAAUGGGAAUUUUUACAUAUGCUAAAAAAAUUAAAAUAAAAACACUGUAUCCGUGUCUCUUCAGAAAUCUUUUGUAUUACUUCUCUUUUGUCACCAAAAAAAAUAUUCAGUACAACUCUUAGAUGUUAAUGAAAGAAAAAACACAUUAUUUAUUUCUUCUCGUAUUUUUCUUUUCGCUCUUUCUGAGAGACAGAGGAUCUGACAUAAUGCAAAAUUUAAGACAAAAAAAAAAAUACCUGGAAGAAAUGAGCAUGGAGAGGGAGUAAUUUUGAAUGAUUAUGCUUUCCCAAUUCCUCUGUAAGCCUCCUUUUUUUCCCCAAACUGUAUUUAGCAUUGUUCCUGAAUCAACAAAAACAUUGCCUUACUCUUAGCUUUUUAUAACACCAAUAAUGAACAAUGUGACAAGAAUAUUCAUAUCUGGGGAGAAAUAGGAUGUAAGAUUUUGAAAGUUCAAGGUGCUAAAUUUUUUGAACUCAUUACAUAUUUGGAUAAUUCUUAAAUUAGCAUUUAUUGGCUGAUGAUGUUUUGAUCAGGAAAAAUUAUCAAGAACAUUUGAUUUUUUACUAAAUUGUAUGUGUUCAGACACUCAAAAUUCUUUGUUGGGGCUCUAGGAAUACUCAGAUCUGAUCACAUUUUAAGAAAUUUUAUCAUUCAGAUUCGUUUACUAAAACUCAUCAGUAAUGAGUUCUGUAUGUUUUGUUGUUAUUUAUGUUUAUCCAAGCUGUUAUGUUGACCUUUUAAAAAUGCUGUUUCUCCUUAAAAUUAAGAAUAACUAUUUUUCCCUUCUUUUAGAAAGCUAAGGAGGAAAUGUGGACCUGAUAGCUGCAAAAGCAAAUUGAACUAAAAUAAAAAGUUCGGAGUUCAAGGACUCCAAACUUUUCAAUCGGUUUUCUCUUCUUCUUUAUUAAAUGUAUUGCCACUAGAAGCAAAUAACUGAUGCAGUUUCUGCCAGAUAAUGGCAAUAAUAAAGGUGAAAUGUGAAUAUUUUUUAAAUUAUAUCUAAAAUCAUCCACAUCAUUUAGCUUGUGGAUGUACAGGUAGUUUCUAUUUGGGAGUGGGGCUAGGUAACUCAUCAUUAUAAAAAUGGUAUCCAAGCAAGGAUCACAAUACCUGUACCACUGCCAUUGUAAACAUUGGAUGGCAAUAUACAUGAAACUGAUGAACAUGAGAACAAAACAAAAUAAAAAGUGUAAUACAUUUUAUUUAUGCUCCAUGGGAGGUGGUAACCUGUGGGGAUCAGCACACUCAGCAAGCGGUCCCCGCGCAUUAGAGGUGAAUCAGACACUUGAACAUCUGUCCACUUCAUGGAAGACGUUUCAUCUCAGAAUACACGUACUAAUAAACAACAGUUGGAGACAAUUGUCUCUGACAUUCAACAUAAUGCUGAGCUGAGGCUGAAAGAAGGAAGGGUGGAAUUGUAUUUCCUUUGGUAAAGCAAAAACAGCCGUGAGUACAGCCUCUUCUAAAAAUCUGAUAUUUAAAGAGAAUUGUAAGACAUCAAAAUGUUCAAUUUGGAAUGAAGAGUGGCCGAAGUUACUGGAAAGCUCGUGCCUCCGUCUGCAAAAUCACUGGCCAGGAAAGCAAAAACUUUUCCAACACCCAAUUUUAAUAUUGUGCUAAAGCUAUUGACUCUGUUAAACCUCUAGAGUUAAAUAUGAUCCCCUCCCCAGCCCCCACCUUUUCUCUCUUAGGUUAGUGUCUGGGGGACAAGGAGGGGGCUGGAGCUUGGCCCCAACCUCGGAAUUGCUGCCAAGGGCUUGUAAUACAAUCUCUCCCCGUUUGAAGGGUAAAUCAGUGUCAACUGCAUUUGCGUCCACCAAAAAAAGUAUUACAAGUGGAUAAAUAAUGUGCACUGCUCUGAGCCCAAAGGUACGCAGUGGACCUGGCCUCUCUGAUAUGCAUCAGUAUAGCCAAUGGCUAGCCAGCAGACAUGAAGCUAAUUUGCUACCAAUGAAAGAAGAUCUGGCCUUGUGGUUAACCAAUCUAUUAGGGAAGGAGAUUACAGCAGAAACUUUUAUGGAGAAGUUGGACAAUGGUGCCUUGCUCUGUCAACUUGCAGAAACUAUGCAGGAGAAAUUCAAGGAGAGCAUGGAUGCUAACAAGCCCACAAAGAAUCUACCGUUGAAGAAGAUCCCAUGCAAAACCAGUGCACCCUCGGGCUCCUUUUUUGCCAGAGACAAUACAGCAAAUUUCUUAUCCUGGUGCCGAGAUUUAGGGGUGGAUGAAACGUGUCUAUUUGAAUCGGAAGGUUUGGUCCUCCACAAGCAACCCAGAGAAGUGUGUCUCUGUCUGCUAGAGCUUGGCCGGAUUGCAGCCAGGUAUGGUGUGGAGCCUCCUGGUUUGAUAAAGCUGGAAAAAGAGAUUGAACAAGAAGAAACACUUUCUGCCCCUUCUCCUUCACCUUCUCCUUCAUCAAAGUCUUCUGGAAAAAAGAGUACAGGAAACUUACUGGAUGAUGCAGUGAAACGAAUUUCUGAAGAUCCUCCUUGCAAAUGCCCAAACAAGUUCUGUGUGGAGCGGCUCUCCCAAGGAAGAUACCGAGUGGGAGAAAAGAUCCUCUUCAUUAGGGGUCUUCAUGGUUGUGACUAUAUCUCCACAGCCAAAGCAAAGCAGACAUUUAAGAUGCUGCACAACAAACAUGUCAUGGUCCGUGUGGGAGGAGGCUGGGAAACUUUUGCAGGGUAUUUGUUGAAACACGACCCCUGCCGAAUGCUGCAGAUCUCCCGUGUGGAUGGCAAAACAUCCCCUAUCCAAAGCAAAUCUCCAACUCUAAAGGACAUGAAUCCAGAUAACUACUUGGUGGUCUCUGCCAGUUAUAAGGCUAAGAAGGAAAUUAAGUGAAACAAAUUGGUCAUGACAAGGGGACCCUCAUAAUGGCCUGUAUCCACUUCUCCAGUAUAGUCAGUUUAGUUCAUAUGUUCUGAAAACUGUUUUGGAGAAAGAUAGACAGAAAAAUGUCAUCAUAUUGAAAAAUGUUCAAAGAGUAGCACUAUUUAUUUUUAAUGCUUCUGUAGAAUAUGACCUAUUAAAAGAAAAUCUAAACUCAAAUUUAAAUUAUCCAAAUUUUAGGCAAAUUAUUAUUUCUCAAUAUGCGAACACAGUAUUUAGAACACAAUAUUAGAAACACAAUUCUAACUAAAGAUAAAUAAGGAGAAAACAUUUAGGAUUUGCAGAUAAGUCAACAGAAAGUGCCUGCUUUACACUCAUGAGUAAAAGCACUCCAGACAUUUUUAUAAUUGCAAGAUUUUUAUGCUUUUUUUUUUUUUUUUUUACAAAAUGAUGAUUAGUGUGAUAAUGUGCUGCAAAAAAUAUCCAACAGCACUACACAUAAGUACAGAGUAUUCACAAUAGUAAUAUGUUACUGGAAAGGCCACUUCCGAAAAGUUUACAUUCACUUGGAAGGCUGCCUUAAAGUAUAUCUCUUAUCUAUGACCAAAUAUCUGGGGUACUUUUAGAAGUUUUCAGUACACCCCCUUAGAGAAUAGCUUAUGAGUUAUUUCACACAUUCCUGAGCACAUGGCUGUGUUUAGAAUGAUCUAGUGUAAUUCAUACAUGAGCUGACAUACGUUGAUACUUUGACGAGUAAAUUGUACAGUCAAAUGUUCAUUGAUUUCAUGUUAUUUCAAAGCAUUUUCUUAUUAAAAAUAUAUCUUUAGUUAAUCCUAUUUUGCUAUGCUUUCUAGUAAAGUAAAUUCACUGUAGCUAAUGAUGUUACAGACUUACGUAUACCCUUGUAUACCUGGGACAGGGCUGUUUUAUACCAAUAAACAGCAAAAUAUUGUCCUUACUCAUUCAAGAAUUAAAAGGAUAAAUUUUAAAAAUGUUAUCUGUCUCUAAAUCAAUGCCUCAUUCUGAAAUCAAGUUAAUUUUCAAAUGGCAA